AACGGGCUCAUUCAGCGGUCGCGAGCUGCCCGCGAGGGGGAGCGGCCGGACGGAGAGCGCGACCCGUCCCGGGGGUGGGGCCGGGCGCAGCGGCGAGAGGAGGCGAAGGUGGCUGCGGUAGCAGCAGCGCGGCAGCCUCGGACCCAGCCCGGAGCGCAGGGCGGCCGCUGCAGGUCCCCGCUCCCCUCCCCGUGCGUCCGCCCAUGGCCGCCGCCGGGCAGCUGUGCUUGCUCUACCUGUCGGCGGGGCUCCUGUCCCGGCUCGGCGCAGCCUUCAACUUGGACACUCGGGAGGACAACGUGAUCCGGAAAUAUGGAGACCCCGGGAGCCUCUUCGGCUUCUCGCUGGCCAUGCACUGGCAACUGCAGCCCGAGGACAAGCGGCUGUUGCUCGUGGGGGCCCCGCGGGCAGAAGCGCUUCCACUGCAGAGAGCCAACAGAACGGGAGGGCUGUACAGCUGCGACAUCACCGCCCGGGGGCCAUGCACGCGGAUCGAGUUUGAUAACGAUGCUGACCCCACGUCAGAAAGCAAGGAAGAUCAGUGGAUGGGGGUCACCGUCCAGAGCCAAGGUCCAGGGGGCAAGGUCGUGACAUGUGCUCACCGAUAUGAAAAAAGGCAGCAUGUUAAUACGAAGCAGGAAUCCCGAGACAUCUUUGGGCGGUGUUAUGUCCUGAGUCAGAAUCUCAGGAUUGAAGACGAUAUGGAUGGGGGAGAUUGGAGCUUUUGUGAUGGGCGAUUGAGAGGCCAUGAGAAAUUUGGCUCUUGCCAGCAAGGUGUAGCAGCUACUUUUACUAAAGACUUUCAUUACAUUGUAUUUGGAGCCCCGGGUACUUAUAACUGGAAAGGGAUUGUUCGUGUAGAGCAAAAGAAUAACACUUUUUUUGACAUGAACAUCUUUGAAGAUGGGCCUUAUGAAGUUGGUGGAGAGACUGAGCAUGAUGAAAGUCUCGUUCCUGUUCCUGCUAACAGUUACUUAGGUUUUUCUUUGGACUCAGGGAAAGGUAUUGUUUCUAAAGAUGAGAUCACUUUUGUAUCUGGUGCUCCCAGAGCCAAUCACAGUGGAGCCGUGGUUUUGCUGAAGAGAGACAUGAAGUCUGCACAUCUCCUCCCUGAGCACAUAUUCGAUGGAGAAGGUCUGGCCUCUUCAUUUGGCUAUGAUGUGGCGGUGGUGGACCUCAACAAGGAUGGGUGGCAAGAUAUAGUUAUUGGAGCCCCACAGUAUUUUGAUAGAGAUGGAGAAGUUGGAGGUGCAGUGUAUGUCUACAUGAACCAGCAAGGCAGAUGGAAUAAUGUGAAGCCAAUUCGUCUUAAUGGAACCAAAGAUUCUAUGUUUGGCAUUGCAGUAAAAAAUAUUGGAGAUAUUAAUCAAGAUGGCUACCCAGAUAUUGCAGUUGGAGCUCCGUAUGAUGACUUGGGAAAGGUUUUUAUCUAUCAUGGAUCUGCAAAUGGAAUAAAUACCAAACCAACACAGGUUCUCAAGGGUAUAUCACCUUAUUUUGGAUAUUCAAUUGCUGGAAACAUGGACCUUGAUCGAAAUUCCUACCCUGAUGUUGCUGUUGGUUCCCUCUCAGAUUCAGUAACUAUUUUCAGAUCCCGGCCUGUGAUUAAUAUUCAGAAAACCAUCACAGUAACUCCUAACAGAAUUGACCUCCGCCAGAAAACAGCGUGUGGGGCGCCUAGUGGGAUAUGCCUCCAGGUUAAAUCCUGUUUUGAAUAUACUGCUAACCCCGCUGGUUAUAAUCCUUCAAUAUCAAUUGUGGGCACACUUGAAGCUGAAAAAGAAAGAAGAAAAUCUGGGCUAUCCUCAAGAGUUCAGUUUCGAAACCAAGGUUCUGAGCCCAAAUAUACUCAAGAACUAACUCUGAAGAGGCAGAAACAGAAAGUGUGCAUGGAGGAAACCCUGUGGCUACAGGAUAAUAUCAGAGAUAAACUGCGUCCCAUUCCCAUAACUGCCUCAGUGGAGAUCCAAGAGCCAAGCUCUCGUAGGCGAGUGAAUUCACUUCCAGAAGUUCUUCCAAUUCUGAAUUCAGAUGAACCCAAGACAGCUCAUAUUGAUGUUCACUUCUUAAAAGAGGGAUGUGGAGACGACAAUGUAUGUAACAGCAACCUUAAACUAGAAUAUAAAUUUUGCACCCGAGAAGGAAAUCAAGACAAAUUUUCUUAUUUACCAAUUCAAAAAGGUGUACCAGAACUAGUUCUAAAAGAUCAGAAGGAUAUUGCUUUAGAAAUAACAGUGACAAACAGCCCUUCCAACCCAAGGAAUCCCACAAAAGAUGGCGAUGACGCCCAUGAGGCUAAACUGAUUGCAACGUUUCCAGACACUUUAACCUAUUCUGCAUAUAGAGAACUGAGGGCUUUCCCUGAGAAACAGUUGAGUUGUGUUGCCAACCAGAAUGGCUCGCAAGCUGACUGUGAGCUCGGAAAUCCUUUUAAAAGAAAUUCAAAUGUCACUUUUUAUUUGGUUUUAAGUACAACUGAAGUCACCUUUGACACCCCAGAUCUGGAUAUUAAUCUGAAGUUAGAAACAACAAGCAAUCAAGAUAAUUUGGCUCCAAUUACAGCUAAAGCAAAAGUGGUUAUUGAACUGCUUUUAUCGGUCUCGGGAGUUGCUAAACCUUCCCAGGUGUAUUUUGGAGGUACAGUUGUUGGCGAGCAAGCUAUGAAAUCUGAAGAUGAAGUGGGAAGUUUAAUAGAGUAUGAAUUCAGGGUAAUAAACUUAGGUAAACCUCUUACAAACCUCGGCACAGCAACCUUGAACAUUCAGUGGCCAAAAGAAAUUAGCAAUGGGAAAUGGUUGCUUUAUUUGGUGAAAGUAGAAUCCAAAGGAUUGGAAAAGGUAACUUGUGAGCCACAAAAGGAGAUAAACUCCCUGAACCUAACGGAGUCUCACAACUCAAGAAAGAAACGGGAAAUUACUGAAAAACAGAUAGAUGAUAACAGAAAAUUUUCUUUAUUUGCUGAAAGAAAAUACCAGACUCUUAACUGUAGCGUGAACGUGAACUGUGUGAACAUCAGAUGCCCGCUGCGGGGGCUGGACAGCAAGGCGUCUCUUAUUUUGCGCUCGAGGUUAUGGAACAGCACAUUUCUAGAGGAAUAUUCCAAACUGAACUACUUGGACAUUCUCAUGCGAGCCUUCAUUGAUGUGACUGCUGCUGCCGAAAAUAUCAGGCUGCCAAAUGCAGGCACUCAGGUUCGAGUGACUGUGUUUCCCUCAAAGACUGUAGCUCAGUAUUCGGGAGUACCUUGGUGGAUCAUCCUAGUGGCUAUUCUCGCUGGGAUCUUGAUGCUUGCUUUAUUAGUGUUUAUACUAUGGAAGUGUGGUUUCUUCAAGAGAAAUAAGAAAGAUCAUUAUGAUGCCACAUAUCACAAGGCUGAGAUCCAUGCUCAGCCAUCUGAUAAAGAGAGGCUUACUUCUGAUGCAUAGUAUUGAUCUACUUCUGUAAUUGUGUGGAUUCUUUAAACGCUCUAGGUACGAUGACAGUGUUCCCCGAUACCAUGCUGUAAGGAUCCGGAAAGAAGAGCGAGAGAUCAAAGAUGAAAAGUAUAUUGAUAACCUUGAAAAAAAACAGUGGAUCACAAAGUGGAACGAAAAUGAAAGCUACUCAUAGCGGGGGCCUAAAAAAAAAAAGCUUCACAGUACCCAAACUGCUUUUUCCAACUCAGAAAUUCAAUUUGGAUUUAAAAGCCUGCUCAAUCCCUGAGGACUGAUUUCAGAGUGACUACACACAGUACGAACCUACAGUUUUAACUGUGGAUAUUGUUACGUAGCCUAAGGCUCCUGUUUUGCACAGCCAAAUUUAAAACUGUUGGAAUGGAUUUUUCUUUAACUGCCGUAAUUUAACUUUCUGGGUUGCCUUUAUUUUUGGCGUGGCUGACUUACAUCAUGUGUUGGGGAAGGGCCUGCCCAGUUGCACUCAGGUGACAUCCUCCAGAUAGUGUAGCUGAGGAGGCACCUACACUCACCUGCACUAACAGAGUGGCCGUCCUAACCUCGGGCCUGCUGCGCAGACGUCCAUCACGUUAGCUGUCCCACAUCACAAGACUAUGCCAUUGGGGUAGUUGUGUUUCAACGGAAAGUGCUGUCUUAAACUAAAUGUGCAAUAGAAGGUGAUGUUGCCAUCCUACCGUCUUUUCCUGUUUCCUAGCUGUGUGAAUACCUGCUCACGUCAAAUGCAUACAAGUUUCAUUCUCCCUUUCACUAAAACACACAGGUGCAACAGACUUGAAUGCUAGUUAUACUUAUUUGUAUAUGGUAUUUAUUUUUUCUUUUCUUUACAAACCAUUUUGUUAUUGACUAACAGGCCAAAGAGUCUCCAGUUUACCCUUCAGGUUGGUUUAAUCAAUCAGAAUUAGAGCAUGGGAGGUCAUCACUUUGACCUAAAUUAUUUACUGCAAAAAGAAAAUCUUUAUAAAUGUACCAGAGAGAGUUGUUUUAAUAACUUAUCUAUAAACUAUAACCUCUCCUUCAUGACAGCCUCCACCCCACAACCCAAAAGGUUUAAGAAAUAGAAUUAUAACUGUAAAGAUGUUUAUUUCAGGCAUUGGAUAUUUUUUACUUUAGAAGCCUGCAUAAUGUUUCUGGAUUUCAUACUGUAACAUUCAGGAAUUCUUGGAGAAAAUGGGUUUAUUCACUGAACUCUAGUGCGGUUUACUCACUGCUGCAAAUACUGUAUAUUCAGGACUUGAAAGAAAUGGUGAAUGCCUAUGGUGGAUCCAAACUGAUCCAGUAUAAGACUACUGAAUCUGCUACCAAAACAGUUAAUCAGUGAGUCGAUGUUCUAUUUUUUGUUUUGUUUCCUCCCCUAUCUGUAUUCCCAAAAAUUACUUUGGGGCUAAUUUAACAAGAACUUUAAAUUGUGUUUUAAUUGUAAAAAUGGCAGGGGGUGGAAUUAUUACUCUAUACAUUCAACAGAGACUGAAUAGAUAUGAAAGCUGAUUUUUUUUAAUUACCAUGCUUCACAAUGUUAAGUUAUAUGGGGAGCAACAGCAAACAGGUGCUAAUUUGUUUUGGAUAUAGUAUAAGCAGUGUCUGUGUUUUGAAAGAAUAGAACACAGUUUGUAGUGCCACUGUUGUUUUGGGGGGGCUUUUUUCUUUUCGGAAAUCUUAAACCUUAAGAUACUAAGGACGUUGUUUUGGUUGUACUUUGGAAUUCUUAGUCACAAAAUAUAUUUUGUUUACAAAAAUUUCUGUAAAACAGGUUAUAACAGUGUUUAAAGUCUCAGUUUCUUGCUUGGGGAACUUGUGUCCCUAAUGUGUUUAGAUUGCUAGAUUGCUAAGGAGCUGAUACUUUGACAGUGUUUUUAGACCUGUGUUACUAAAAAAAAGAUGAAUGUCCUGAAAAGGGUGUUGGGAGGGUGGUUCAACAAAGAAACAAAGAUGUUAUGGUGUUUAGAUUUAUGGUUGUUAAAAAUGUCAUCUCAAGUCAAGUCACUGGUCUGUUUGCAUUUGAUACAUUUUUGUACUAACUAGCAUUGUAAAAUUAUUUCAUGAUUAGAAAUUACCUGUGGAUAUUUGUAUAAAAGUGUGAAAUAAAUUUUUUAUAAAAGUGUUCAUUGUUUCGUAACACAGCAUUGUAUAUGUGAAGCAAACUCUAAAAUUAUAAAUGACAACCUGAAUUAUCUAUUUCAUCAAACCAAAGUUCAGUGUUUUUAUUUUUGGUGUCUCAUGUAAUCUCAGAUCAGCCAAAGAUACUAGUGCCAAAGCAAUGGGAUUCGGGGUUUUUUUCUGUUUUCGCUCUAUGUAGGUGAUCCUCAAGUCUUUCAUUUUCCUUCUUUAUGAUUAAAAGAAACCUACAGGUAUUUAACAACCUACAAA